AGUGUGGUGAGCGAGCCGAAGCGCGGGAAGCAGCUCUUGUGGAUCCUCAGUGGCGGAGGCUCGGUCACCCGGAUAGGUAAAGGAAAACAUGCCUGCCACACGGAAGCCAAUGAGAUAUGGGCAUACAGAGGGACACACGGAGGUCUGUUUUGAUGAUUCUGGGAGUUUUAUUGUGACUUGUGGAAGUGAUGGUGAUGUGAGGAUUUGGGAAGACUUGGAUGAUGAUGAUCCUAAGUUCAUUAAUGUUGGAGAAAAGGCAUAUUCAUGUGCUUUGAAGAGUGGAAAACUGGUCACUGCAGUUUCUAAUAAUACUAUUCAAGUCCACACAUUUCCUGAAGGAGUUCCAGAUGGUAUAUUGACUCGCUUCACUACAAAUGCAAACCAUGUGGUCUUUAAUGGGGAUGGUACUAAAAUUGCUGCUGGAUCUAGUGAUUUUCUAGUCAAAAUUGUGGAUGUGAUGGAUAGCAGCCAACAGAAAACAUUUCGAGGACAUGAUGCCCCUGUUUUAAGUCUUUCCUUUGAUCCUAAGGACAUCUUUCUGGCAUCAGCUAGUUGUGAUGGAUCUGUCAGAGUGUGGCAAAUUUCAGAUCAGACAUGUGCUAUUAGUUGGCCACUGCUACAAAAAUGCAACGAUGUGAUAAAUGCAAAAUCAAUCUGCAGACUUGCUUGGCAGCCAAAAAGUGGGAAGUUACUGGCAAUUCCUGUGGAAAAAUCUGUUAAGCUAUAUAGAAGAGAAUCUUGGAGUCAUCAAUUUGAUCUUUCAGAUAAUUUCAUCUCUCAGACCCUCAAUAUAGUAACCUGGUCUCCCUGUGGGCAAUAUUUAGCUGCAGGUAGUAUUAAUGGUCUAAUCAUAGUUUGGAAUGUGGAAACCAAAGACUGCAUGGAAAGGGUGAAACAUGAGAAAGGUUAUGCAAUUUGUGGUCUGGCAUGGCAUCCUACUUGUGGUCGAAUAUCGUAUACUGAUGCGGAAGGAAAUCUAGGGCUUCUAGAGAAUGUUUGUGACCCCAGUGGAAAGACAUCAAGCAGUAAGGUAUCUAGCAGAGUGGAAAAGGAUUAUAAUGAUCUUUUUGAUGGAGAUGAUAUGAGUAAUGCUGGUGAUUUUCUAAAUGACAAUGCAGUUGAGAUCCCUUCUUUUUCAAAAGGGAUUAUAAAUGAUGAUGAGGAUGAUGAAGACCUCAUGAUGGCUUCAGGUCGUCCUAGACAGCGAAGUCACAUCCUAGAAGAUGAUGAAAACUCAGUUGAUAUUUCAAUGCUAAAAACUGGUUCUAGUCUUCUCAAAGAGGAGGAGGAAGAUGGUCAAGAAGGCAGCAUUCACAAUCUACCACUUGUAACAUCCCAAAGGCCAUUUUAUGAUGGACCCAUGCCAACUCCCCGGCAAAAGCCAUUUCAGUCAGGUUCUACACCGUUGCAUCUCACUCACAGAUUCAUGGUGUGGAACUCUAUUGGAAUUAUUCGCUGCUAUAAUGAUGAGCAAGACAAUGCCAUAGAUGUGGAGUUCCAUGAUACCUCCAUACACCAUGCAACACACUUAUCAAACACUUUGAAUUAUACAAUAGCAGAUCUUUCCCACGAAGCUAUUUUGUUGGCAUGUGAAAGCACUGAUGAACUAGCAAGCAAGCUUCACUGCCUGCACUUUAGUUCUUGGGAUUCAAGCAAAGAGUGGAUAAUAGACUUGCCUCAGAAUGAGGAUAUUGAAGCCAUAUGUCUCGGUCAAGGAUGGGCUGCUGCCGCUACUAGUGCCCUGCUUCUUCGAUUGUUUACUAUUGGAGGGGUUCAAAAAGAGGUAUUCAGCCUUGCUGGACCUGUGGUGUCAAUGGCAGGACAUGGAGAACAGCUUUUCAUUGUUUAUCACAGAGGUACAGGAUUUGAUGGGGAUCAGUGCCUUGGAGUUCAACUGCUAGAGCUGGGGAAAAAGAAAAAACAAAUUUUGCAUGGUGACCCUCUUCCUCUUACAAGGAAAUCCUACCUUGCAUGGAUUGGGUUUUCAGCUGAAGGUACCCCUUGUUACGUGGAUUCAGAAGGAAUUGUUCGAAUGCUUAACAGAGGACUUGGUAAUACGUGGACUCCUAUAUGUAAUACAAGAGAGCACUGCAAAGGAAAAUCUGAUCACUACUGGGUGGUUGGUAUCCAUGAAAAUCCCCAGCAACUAAGGUGCAUUCCUUGUAAAGGUUCUCGGUUUCCCCCAACCCUUCCACGCCCUGCUGUUGCUAUAUUAUCCUUUAAGCUUCCUUACUGUCAGAUUGCAACAGAGAAAGGACAAAUGGAGGAGCAAUUUUGGCGUUCAGUUAUAUUUCACAACCACCUUGAUUAUUUAGCUAAAAAUGGUUAUGAAUAUGAAGAGAGCACUAAAAAUCAAGCAACAAAAGAGCAACAGGAACUUUUAAUGAAAAUGCUUGCGCUUUCUUGUAAACUGGAGCGAGAAUUCCGUUGUGUGGAACUUGCUGAUCUAAUGACUCAAAAUGCUGUGAAUUUAGCCAUUAAAUAUGCUUCUCGCUCUCGGAAAUUAAUACUGGCUCAAAAACUAAGUGAACUGGCUGUAGAGAAGGCAGCCGAAUUGACAGCAACCCAGGUGGAAGAGGAAGAAGAAGAAGAAGAUUUCAGAAAAAAGCUGAAUGCUGGUUACAGCAAUACUGCUACAGAGUGGAGCCAACCAAGGUUCAGAAAUCAAGUUGAAGAAGAUGCUGAGGACAGUGGAGAAGCUGAUGAUGAAGAAAAACCAGAAAUACAUAAGCCUGGACAGAACUCGUUUUCCAAAAGUACAAAUUCCUCUGAUGUUUCAGCUAAGUCAGGUGCAGUUACCUUUAGCAGCCAAGGACGAGUAAAUCCCUUUAAGGUAUCAGCCAGUUCCAAAGAACCAGCCAUGUCAAUGAAUUCAGCACGUUCAACUAAUAUUUUAGACAAUAUGGGCAAAUCAUCCAAGAAAUCCACUGCACUUAGUCGAACUACAAAUAAUGAAAAGUCUCCCAUUAUAAAGCCUCUGAUUCCAAAGCCGAAGCCUAAGCAGGCAUCUGCAGCAUCCUAUUUCCAGAAAAGAAAUUCUCAAACUAAUAAAACUGAGGAAGUGAAAGAAGAAAAUCUUAAAAAUGUAUUAUCUGAAACCCCAGCUAUAUGUCCUCCUCAAAACACUGAAAACCAAAGGCCAAAGACCGGGUUCCAGAUGUGGUUAGAAGAAAAUAGAAGUAAUAUUUUGUCUGACAAUCCUGACUUUUCAGAUGAAGCAGACAUAAUAAAAGAAGGAAUGAUUCGAUUUAGAGUAUUGUCAACUGAAGAAAGAAAGGUGUGGGCUAACAAAGCCAAAGGAGAAACGGCAAGUGAAGGAACUGAAGCAAAGAAGCGAAAACGUGUGGUUGAUGAAAGUGAUGAAACAGAAAACCAGGAAGAAAAAGCAAAAGAGAACCUGAAUUUGUCUAAAAAGCAGAAACCUUUAGAUUUUUCUACAAAUCAGAAACUAUCAGCUUUUGCAUUUAAGCAGGAGUAAAGGAAGAAAGUGACCCUAGGGAAGUAAUGGAUUUUUUUUUACUCAUCUUUGAAUAUAGACUCGAGUCUUUGGGAAACUCAUUAUAUAUAUAUUUUUUAAAGAGUUUGAAGCAACUGUUUGUCUUUAUAAGAUAAUGUAGUAAUUAUAUUGGUGUAGGUAACAGGACAUAUGUAAAAACUAUCAUCUUUGCAGAUUACUCUGCCUCCAAAUGCAGGGCCUUUCAGAGAUGCAUUGUGAUUGUAAUUACUGAGUUGAAGCUCCAACCAAUUUGAAUUUGUUUCUUAACCUUGAAAAAUCAUUAAAGCCAAGGUAUUAAAACCUUUGUGCAUUAAUACCUUCUAGGGGUUUGGUUCAUUUGGUUUUUGUCAUGUGCAAGGAAGGACAAUAGUCCUCUUUCCAAGUGUGUUAGCAUAGACUUCUCUAUAUGUUUCUACUAGACCUAGGGGAUGACGUCUUUUAAUAAUACUGGCCCUAAACAUGUAAAUAAUCUUGUAGGUGAGACUUUUUCUUUUGUGUUUCGGAAAUUUCCUAUGUGGCUUUCAGUUGUCUGUUUGUAUAGCCUGGAUUUUUUUGAGGUAAAUGAAACUUUCUCAUUUGUAUAUUUGGCUUGAUAUGGUCUUAAUAUUAUCUUUCCACGAAAUGGAUAUAUUUCUAGAAAAUAUAUAUUUACUACCAUAAUUUCUACCACCACCCCCAUUUUGCUCUGCAUUAUACACAGUAGAGAAGAACUGAAGACACUGCUGUGACAGUAUUGCAGUCCAAGGCAUCAUGUGCUCUUGGUGGGAUACUCUGAUUAUCAGCAUCAACAGUACUUUACUGAGCAAGACUUUGAAGGCCUGAGAAGAGAGCAAAGUUAUGGAAAGUAUUUAACUCUUAUUUUAUAUUGAACAAACAAGGUUUAAUCAUGUCAUACAUUUUUGGUUUUCUAAGCAGAGACUAAUACAAAUGCAGCCACAUAAAGGCAGUGUACUGGGGGUGGGAGGGAAGGAAACAAUCACAUAAAAUCAGCUGACUCAAAAUUGAGGAUAGUUAAUAGGUUGAAAGGGAAAAAGUAUGUUGAAAAUUUAGACAUAAAUGAACCAAGAAUAUUCCUUAUCUGGUGAUGAUUAAAGUUAGGAAAACAUACAUUUUUUAUUUUUUAAUUAGUAGCUGCUAUCAGAGACAUUAUAGCACAGUGGUUAUGAGCACAGAUUCCAAAGCCAGAUUACCUAGGUUCGGAGACCCGCUUCUCUACCUACUACUAAUAGUUGGGUCAUGUUGGGCCGGUGACCCAAAUUCUAGCCUUCAUUCACUCAUCUGUAAAAUGGAUAUAAUGAUAGUACCUACUUUAUAGGUUGUUAUGAGAAUUGAAUGAAAUGAAAGCCCUUAGUUUCUGACACAUAGUAAUCUUUUAUAUAAAUGUUAGUUACUAUUCUGAUAAUGAUGAUGCUGUUGGUUAUUUCAUCUUGCUUUGUCAUUAGGUUUGAUUCUGAAUACUAUACAAACUAAUUUUGAUUUCAAGAUCUUAAGUAAAGGUUUAUUUAUAGUACAUUGGAAAGCAUGUUUGUAGACAUGUAUUUUGUGUUUGGUUCCUCAACUUGCUUUGUAUAUAUUUUAUAAUACUAGGUUGAUAUAAAAGUAAAUGCAGUUUCGCCAUUUCAGUGGCAAAAACCGCGAUUUCUUUUGUGCCAACCUAAUGCUUAAGGAUAUAAUCUGUGUAUAUUGUAUUUCAGAUUCAUAGCAACCUAAUAACAAGGAUUUACAAAAGGGUUUUUACUUCCCUACUUUUUUUUGGCUGAAGGAAGGUUUUUGUAUUGACUUGGUUUAACUUACAAAUCAGAACUUUGAAACCAAGAAACAUUAUCCUUAUUUCUCUGCUAUAUAAUAGUAAACCUGUUUUUUUCCAGUGUUCUUUUUUUUUUUUCCAGAGAAUUGGGACUGAAUAGUAUGAAAGUGAAAAUGGAAAUAAAUUAAUUAUUAAUCAUCAUCAUAUCAAUAAUAUUGCCUACUUGAGCUUAUUGUAUACUAUAGAAAAUUGACAUAUACUUAAUUUUAUUCUCCAAAAGCAAAAACUCCUCACAGGAGGUUACUUUACAGAUUUAUUUUGGAGAACAAGUGAAUAGGCACUGGGGUUAUGUGCAGCUCUGGGGACUGUGCUAUGAUCUAAAGCCUCUCAUAUCUGUGCAGCAACCUGGGGUGAGUCACUGUCACUAACAUGGAACAGAUGCCAGGUAGUCCCUUUGGACAAAAGGAUGAGGCCCAUCCAUGUAGAAAGCAUCUUAAUCAGUGACUGUCUUAUGGGCCCUCUUUGUUUCCCAUCUGUUUUAUUAUCAGAAUAUAUAAUUUUCCCCCAAGUUUUCAUCUUGAAUCUCUCAAACCUACAGAAAAUUUGAAAUUUGACAGUAAGCACCUGUAUAUCCUUCCUCUAGUUUGUCUUAUUGUUGACAUUUUAUCAUGUAUGCUUUAUAGACAGGAUUUUUCCUGAACCAUUUGGAAUAUGCAUAUACUUCAUCCCUCAGUUCCCAGCAUGUACCCUAAGAAUAAAGAUUUUCUUCUGCAUAA